AAUGCAAGCCUGAGCUCUCCCGCCAUAAGGCUGCAGCGGUGUGGGCUCCUUGUGCCCAGAUCCUUUGUAUUCAUAGGGGGAAGUGGAAGACCACGCUGCCUGACUGAGACUUUAUUAUAGAGGCUCAGGAAAAAGAUGAACUGGUCCCAUUCCUGCAUCUCCUUUUGCUGGAUCUACUUUGCUGCUUCCAGACUGAGAGCUGCAGAGACGGCAGAUGGAAAAUAUGCUCAGAAGUUGUUUAAUGACCUUUUUGAAGAUUAUUCUAAUGCUCUUCGUCCAGUGGAAGAUACAGAUAAAGUCCUGAAUGUGACCCUGCAGAUUACGCUCUCUCAGAUUAAGGAUAUGGAUGAAAGAAACCAAAUUCUGACUGCUUAUUUGUGGAUCCGCCAAAUCUGGCACGAUGCCUAUCUCACGUGGGACCGAGAUCAGUACGAUGGCCUAGACUCCAUCAGGAUCCCCAGUGACCUCGUGUGGAGGCCAGACAUCGUCUUAUAUAACAAGGCUGAUGAUGAAUCUUCAGAGCCUGUGAACACCAAUGUGGUCCUGCGGUAUGAUGGGCUGAUCACCUGGGAUGCACCGGCCAUCACCAAAAGCUCCUGUGUGGUGGAUGUCACCUACUUCCCUUUUGACAACCAGCAGUGCAACCUGACUUUUGGUUCCUGGACCUACAAUGGCAAUCAGGUGGACAUAUUCAACGCCUUGGACAGCGGAGAUCUCUCUGACUUCAUUGAAGAUGUGGAAUGGGAGGUCCAUGGCAUGCCCGCUGUGAAGAAUGUGAUCUCCUAUGGCUGCUGCUCUGAGCCUUACCCGGAUGUCACAUUCACCCUCCUUCUGAAGAGGAGGUCCUCGUUCUAUAUCGUCAACCUCCUCAUCCCAUGCGUCCUCAUAUCUUUUCUGGCUCCUCUGAGUUUUUAUCUCCCAGCAGCCUCCGGAGAAAAGGUCUCCCUGGGAGUGACCAUCCUGUUGGCCAUGACUGUAUUUCAGCUAAUGGUGGCAGAAAUCAUGCCGGCCUCAGAAAAUGUGCCCCUGAUAGGUAAAUACUACAUAGCCACGAUGGCCCUGAUCACAGCCUCCACUGCGUUGACCAUCAUGGUGAUGAAUAUCCACUUCUGUGGGGCCGAGGCCCGGCCGGUGCCACACUGGGCCAGGGUGGUCAUCCUGAAAUACAUGUCCAGGGUCUUGUUUGUCUAUGAUGUGGGUGAAAGCUGCCUCAGCCCGCACCACAGUAGAGAGCGGGACCACCUCACGAAAGUUUAUAGCAAACUCCCAGAGUCUAACCUGAAAGCAGCCAGGAACAAAGACCUUUCCAGAAAGAAGGACAUGAACAAACGCUUAAAGAACGACCUGGGCUGCCAGGGUAAGAACCCUCAGGAGGCCGAGAGUUACUGUGCACAGUACAAAGUGCUGACGAGGAAUAUUGAGUACAUCGCCAAGUGCCUCAAAGACCACAAGGCCACCAAUUCCAAGGGGAGUGAAUGGAAGAAGGUGGCGAAAGUCAUAGACCGAUUCUUCAUGUGGAUUUUUUUCAUUAUGGUGUUUGUGAUGACUAUUUUGAUCAUAGCAAGAGCGGAUUAGUCACAGAUAUUGGCUUUGCUAUCUGGGUAGAAAUUAAUACAAUUCCCUGUGAUCUAUUCCAAUGUUCUUCCAAGAUUUUUGUUCAUCUAUAAUUUAGGGGUUAUGUUGUCUGUGCUUUUUAUUUUUAGCUUCAAAUGAAUGUCGAAGCUAUCUGCUCUGUUAAAUUAAGCAGAAGAACCAAAAUUUCAAGGGUAGGAAGAUGGAAGAAAUAGGGAAAGAGCCCUUUUAUAGCCCACCGUAGUGGUGGGUGACUGGCCUCUAGUUUAUAUAAUUAUUUACCUCUUUGGCAGUACAGAUAACAAAAUACACUUUACUGGUAAAAUUUAAAACAAAAAAGGCAAAACAAAACAAACUCAUUUUCCCCUUAGUUCCCAUUAAAAUAUGCAUUUGAAAAAUGAAAUAGUCAUAUAUAUAUUAGUGUGAUUUAAGUCUCAAUGGUACCUUAUUCAGGCAUAGUGCAUUUGAAGUCAUAUCUCAAAUAGUGGAAUAAAAGGUUUUGUCCCAUGUAAAGAAAGUCUAAGCAUCAGCUGUUUAAUGGGGAAAAGAACUUUCUUCAUAAUGGUGAUGUCGUAUAUGUUGGUUAUGUUUUAUAUAAACCCAAAAGAUGAAGUCAUUCCUGCAUUUACCCUUUGAUUAAAAUAUGAUAGAUGAAGCUGUUCCUGCAUUUAGUCUUGUAUUAAAAUAAGGUGAUUAGCAA